AACUGGACUUUUGGAUGGCAUUUCUGGACCUGCCCUGGGCCAGAGGGGAGCCCACUACCCUGAAGGGACCUGUGAUGACAUUCCAGGAGCAGGCCCCAUAGGAGGCUCCCUGGACUGUGGAGAAUCACAAUAUUCCUGACUGCCAAAACUUUGGAGAAAGACAGUCAGCAGGUACAAAGUUAGAAAGACAACAAAGAAGACAAAUCUGUGCUGUCACCUGAAGCUGGAGAAACCUUCAAAGAAGAGCUCAGUCACAGCAGUGGACUUUGACCUUGGCACUGAAGAAUGUCUAAAUCUGAAGGAAAUGGACAACGGAAAGACAGAGACACUGGCCACUGUGAAUUUGAACCUUGAGAGAAGGCAGUGCUUUCUACCUUGACUUACCAAAUGGAAGCCCUUCUGAACAGAGAUGGAGCAAGUUUUGAGGAGAGGGACUCCAGAGUCCUGGGACACAGGAGAAUGGUCCUCUCUUGACUUCCCAGGAGUGCGCCUCACACAGCCAUCUGUCCUUGGCUUGAACUCAUUCACUCUUUAGAUUUGGGAACCAAUCCAUGAAAAGAGAGAACUUUACUCUCAUCACUGACUUUGUUUUCCAAGGUUUCUCUAGCUUCCAUGAGCAGCAGAUCACCCUUUUUGGCGUGUUCCUUGCACUAUACAUCUUAACCUUAGCAGGCAAUAUCAUCAUUGUGACCAUCAUCCGAAUGGAUCUUCAUCUUCACACACCCAUGUACUUCUUCCUGAGCAUGCUGUCCACUUCAGAGACUGUAUAUACAUUGGUCAUUCUCCCAAGAAUGCUCUCCAGCCUCGUAGGUAUGAGCCAGCCCAUAUCAUUGGCAGGGUGUGCCACACAGAUGUUCUUUUUUGUAACCUUUGGCAUCACUAACUGCUUCCUGCUCACAGCAAUGGGAUAUGACCGCUAUGUGGCCAUCUGCAACCCCCUGAGAUACAUGGUUAUUAUGAACAAGAGGCUGCGUAUCCAACUUGUCCUGGGGGCCUGCAGCAUUGGGCUGAUUGUAGCAAUAACGCAAGUGACAUCUGUAUUCAGGUUACCCUUCUGUGCUAGAAAGGUGCCCCACUUCUUCUGUGACAUCCGCCCUGUGAUGAAGCUCUCCUGCAUUGACACCACUGUCAAUGAAAUCCUGACUUUGAUUAUCAGUGUGCUGGUGCUUGUUGUACCUAUGGGUCUGGUUUUCAUUUCUUAUGUUCUCAUUAUCUCUACAAUCCUCAAGAUUGCUUCAGUUGAGGGCCGGAAGAAGGCUUUUGCCACCUGUGCAUCCCACCUCACUGUGGUCAUUGUCCACUACAGCUGUGCCUCCAUUGCCUACCUCAAGCCCAAGUCAGAGAACACCAGAGAACAUGACCAGCUGAUCUCGGUGACCUACACUGUCAUCACUCCCCUACUGAACCCUGUGGUAUACACCCUGAGAAAUAAAGAGGUCAAAGAUGCUCUGUGCAGGGCUGUUGGUGGGAAGUUUUCCUGACCAUGUAGGAAGAGUUCUCCUGAGGCUGUCAACAUCCACACUAGGCAGGAAUAUGAGGUGUAAACUCACAAACACUUGGCUCCUAGAGACCUGCCCCUUAAAUAAGAGGCAAAAGAGGAAUAGCAGUUUCAUACAACUGGGAGUCUGAAGCUUUAAAUAAAGUUACUGGAUGGAGUGUUAUCCCUAUUUUUGGGGAUAAAUAGACAAACAAGGAUAAGAUAUGCCUAAAUAAAAGGCCAGAAAGUA